AAAGACCUACAUGUUAGACCUAAAACCAUAAAAUCCCUAGAAGAAAACCUAGGCAUUACCAUUCAGGAUAAUGGUCCACUCUUAUUGUGACCCUCACACUCCUGAAGGAGGGUCAUAACUCAGAUCUGCUUCACUUGACCCUUCUCAGGUUUAGAAAACAAAUUGGUGUGUCCCAAUGUGGGAUCUGUCUUAGAAUAACCUGGAUGGCAGACUGAAAGUGCUGAUUCCUGGGUCCUAUCCUAGAGCUGCUAAAUUUUUGAGAGUGGCGCUUGAAAGGCUACAUUUUAAUCAAACUUUCGGCAUGAAUAUAUUACACACUAUAAAGUUAAUGUACAUAGGGGAGGCCUAGAGGAUACGACUAGGGAUAAAGUAGUGAAUGGCAGAGGCAAUAGUAGGCACCAUAAUAUUUUUCUAAAAAUGCAGAUGGAACCUGACUACAUUUUCAUAAAACUCUUCCAUACGUUUUUGAGGCUUGAGCCAAACGUUGGCCUGACUGCAAGAUAGAACAGUGGAAUGAGGAAGGUGGUGUGGUAUGAUGUGCUGCUAGGCAACAGGUGAAUGAGUAUUUCCUUCCUUUUUGCUAUCAGAAAGCAUAGGGCCACAGCUGGGGGUUGUGGGGUGGGAAUCAGAUUAAAUGCUCUAAUUUUUUUUUUUUUUUUUGCAUUUGCUGAUAGGAUUUACUUGUUUAUAUUUUUAUAAGCCAUGAGUAAAAUAUUUUAAGUGUAUCAAAACAGGGGAUGGGUGGUGAAAGAAUGAUUUUUUAAACAGUGGCAGGGAAAUAAUAACUGAACUAGAAAAAGAUUAUUCACACAUAAAAACCAAUAUAUUUUACUUCACGCUAUUUACACUAUGCUGGUUGUAGUUACUAGUGGCUCAAUGGCAAAUCAGAAUUACAACAAAGAACAGUAACAGAAACAAACCAAAAGCAAACUAAAGAAAAGCAUUAAUUCAUGUUUGAGGCAACUAUUUGAAAAUAGGAAAAUGUUUAGUCAUAGAUCUAUUCCAGUUAAAUGUAUUUGUCUGUCUCUGAGGUCUUAGAAACCAUGGAUUUAAGAGCAACAUGAAUUAAAUGUCCAGGAAGGUGCGAAAUCCCCCAUACUUGUUGCCAAUGCACUGAAGGUUAAGUAAGUCCUGACAAAUCUAAUAUUCUGGAAUUAUCUUGAGGAAAGGGAUGUGCAUUUUUUUCAGUUCAAGUAAGAGAGGGCUAUUGGUUGAGUAGCUGCUGAUGAGAACCUUUCUGGGUCUUCAUUAAGUAGAAGCUAUUAAAUUAACAUUGAAAUAAGAACUUUACAACUUUUCCCCUUCAACAGAUUUGGUAAAUGCAUUUUGACUCUUACAGUUUAAGGGAGAAAAUGAAAUUCUGUUCAAUUGGAAAAGAAUCUACUAAGCCUGGUUUUCUUCCUGCAUAUGAUGCCAUAUAGACACUUAUGUCAGGAGUGCAUAGGUAUGUGUCUCAGGGAGGCUGGCGCAGAGUUUAUGAUACAAGUAUUGGAGUACUGCGAGCUGCCAGAGGAGAGUUCAUUUAUGUGAGCUCUCCACCUUUUGGCUUACCCUAUAACUUCUGCCUGUAAAGAUGCUUGCUUUUAUUCUAUUGUAGGCUUUGUUAUCAAAGGCAGGGGAUAUUUUCUUUUUAAGAUAGCCCUUAGAUGCUUCCUACAGGUUGCGAUUGCUUGAGCAGGGUGGGCAAGCUAGUUUUGUUAUCACACCCUACCCGCUCUCCUAAUUCUCCAGAGAGUAAGUGUUCUUCUUAAAAUUAUAGCUAUGUCGAGUGCCUCUGUGUCUUUAGACACUCUUUUAAUGUGCUAGUAUAAAGUAAAAGUCUUUUUGAAGAUAUGUUUUAUAGGGAGGUGCUUUUGGGAGCCUCUUGAGAUGUUCACUGGUACUGAAUCGAGGUAGCUUUAUGGUGGUUUAAUGACAACAUAGAACACUUGUAAUAAAGUUCCGUGUUGAUAUGUGUCCUAGGGCAUGUUAUAAUUAGAGCGGAUUGAACAUGUUGAUUUUGUUUUCCCCUCUGCUCACAUGGCCCCCUUCGUCUUGUUAGGGUUUUGCAACUGGAGAUCUGUCGGAGGUUUUCUUCAUCCCCUAAAGAUGAAAGAGAUCUCUCACAAUGGAAAUUUGGAAAAUUACACAUACACCUGUGAAAUUAGCGAAUUUGUAUAAAGUUUGUAUUCCAAACAAUAUGCGGGAUCUACAACAAUGCUUUGUUUUAUGUGAGGAUUUUUUUUUUCUGGCUGUGCAAAGAACAAGUGUGCAGGACUGUACAGGCUUAGCGAGAAUAUUCAUCAUUAUUUACUGUGUCAAACCCACAAGGAGGGCCAAACUGGCAGUGUUCCAGGAGCAGGAGGCACACCUAUUUGUGAAAAAUGGAACAGAUUUCUAUCGUUGCCCUCACUUUGACUAUUUGGUUCAAGGUGGUGGUGGUGCUAAGACAUGUCAUUUUGUUAGCCACGUAUGUGGGUUAACAAUGAAGGCUGGCUAUGUUGCUGUCCUGUAAAAUCCCACAGACUACACUUGGUUUGUGCAUGAACCUGAUUAUAAUAAGGUAUUGGAGUGAGGAAUGCUGAGCAGUGGAACAUGUGUGUGAUCUGGCCAGGACCUGUCCCCUCAAUCUGAUUGUCAUUAAUUGAUUAGCGAGCUUUGCCUGGUUGGACAGAGUACCCUUGCUCAUGUCUCAGGAAAUGUUAGGCCCUCAAAAGAGGGGAUGAAGAGAAUGCUUUUGCUGUUGGAAGGUUUUGCUCUUCAGAAGACUCAAACAGCAUGCCAUAAUUUUAAAAAAUUGACAUACUGUCCCCUAGCUUUGUUUUCAUGUCAUAGCCACACAGUGGAAGAUUCUUUAGUAAAACAACAUCCUGGUCAAUUGUUUGCAUUAUCCAGGACUCUUGGCAGAUAUGUAUAAGUAACAUUUGAGAUCAGCCUGAAGUGGCUACAGGUCUAUUCUGUCCCAGAAUCAUCUGAAAGAAUGUUGUUAUUUGAGCAUUUGCUGGACUCUCUGAUGUUAUUUGAAAGAACAAUUAACCAGCACUAAAUGAGUAAACCUAACCUGCCACUUAUCAGGAUUUGUCCAGGUGAAAGGCAGGUUGAUUACAGAUCAUCAGUUGCAGUACACAAAGUGUCUCUCCAUAAUUGAGGAAAGGACUCUGUAUAAACUGUAAAUUAUUGUACUCUUUGUAUUAAAUGACAAUAGUGUAAUAAAUAUAAUUUAUACUAUUACAAAGUGACUUUGGGAUAGCAUUUGUAUUCCAGCACAGUUGUUCUCAAACUUGAGCAUACAUCAGAAUCACCUACAGGAUUUGUUAAAACAUGGAUUGAUGGCCCCAUCCCACAGAGUUUCUGAAAUCGGUAGAUCUGGAGUAGGGUCCAUUUCUAAUUUGCCUUUCUAACAAGUUACCAGGUGAUGCUAUUAUCAGGUGAUGCUAAUGCUGCUGGUCCAGGUACCAAACUUGGAGAACCCUGUGGGCUGAUAAACUGCUUGUAAUCAGCCAAUGAAGCCAGGCAUCAUUUUGGAAGCAGUUAUUUUAUUAAAAUUUCUUUUUGGAAUGUUUUAUCAAUAAUUAAUUGCAUAGGAAAAGAAUCGCUUUAAUAGGGCAGAAUCAGAAUGGGUAUUCUAAAAUGGAGGAUUAUAAAAGAGAAAUUGACCUACUUGAUGAAAUGUGGGCUAGAUACAAAUUGUAUUAAUUUAGAAGAAAAAAGUUUACAUAUGCAAUGACUAAAACCCGAUGCUAAAUUUUUUGUUGAUUUUCUUCUCUAAUUAAAUGUUUCCCCCUCACAUCUUUGUAGUGAAUUGAUUAUCUUUUCUUCAUUUCAUUCAUGUAACUGUAUUGUUACACAUGAAACAAAGAAACGUAUGCUGAAUGUUUUUAAGGACCACUCUUAAUUCAUCUUUGCCCUAUGAAACGAUUUAAGAAACUUGGUCGCCAAAGCCCUUUUUUAGUGUUGUUUGGCUACUGCUUCUGUUGUUGUUUUAAUUUAACCUGUACCUUGUCUGAUUCACUCUAGCAAAAGAAGGAAAUAUAAAUCCAUUCUGGAGUUAAAAGACUCCGUGCCCCAUUUAAAACAUCCUUUUAUACCUAUAUUUAAAAAUAACUUAGAAAUCACUUCCUUUUUACUUGUACUAGCUUAACUUUGUUAUAUAAACAUAUAGGGUAUUAUACACUAAUUUUUGAUGUAAACGUAUUUGAUAGUUUUGCAGAAUGCAGUUUGUUAGAUAAGAAUAGUAGCAAUAUUUUGAUGGUGCUUUGAAAUUUCUAAAGAAAAGUGUAUAUGUGGUAUCUCAUAGAAGUCUAUAAAGUUAUAGAUUUUGAUUAAUUCAUUUAUGCCACAUAAUAUAUAUAAGGAGUUCUGUGUUUAGGUUCAGAUCCUUUCCUUUCUUACUCAUAAGUGCUUUUAAAAAAAUCUAACGUCCUACAUUCAUGCUUUUGAUGUUUUUGUUGUGGUAGCAUUUCUCACUUUGGGGAAAAAAAAAUUGCUGCUUGUCUUAUCUCACAUCUUCAAGAUGACUUCUAGCAGGGUGAGAGUACAUUGAAUAACCAGGAAAGGACCAUGGAUUUCACACUGUUUAGUGGGAUAAACUUUCUCCAACGAUAGUAAAAAUAAUAAUAAUUUGACACUGUGUCUAGAUUUUUUUAAAAUUUGCCCAGUAUUCUCUCACUUUGAUUUGGUCUCCAACUUUAUUAUAAUUAACUUCAAUUGAAAAAUCCUUAUUUUGGUAAAUAUUAAGUGCCUUGGCUAAAUGCAAGGUAAUAUUCUUGCUGCUUUCAGUUGCAAAUGUGGGUAAGAUAGAAUUAUAACAAAGGAAGUAAGAAAAAUGCAUGGGUAGCUGGAAUCUAGGAUAUUAUAUGAGAAGCCUUUCCUGCCCACCCUGCCACCAGUCUCAUAUCUUGUGAAUAAAGUUUGUCUCCUUAACUGGAUUAUCCACUCACUUUGGGCUGGGGCCAUCUUAUCUUAUACGUUGUUGUUAUCUCAGUGCUUGUCACAGUGCCUACCAUGUUUAGCAUCCUCAGUAAAUAUUAUUUAAGUGGAUAAUGAAUAAGUUAAUGAAUAAAUACAUAAAACUCUCAUAAAGAAAAGAGAAUAAGCUAAUAUAUAAUGCCUUUCAUCGUUCGUACUUAUUUUCUGUUAGGAGCUUUUUAUUAUUGAAAUAUAUCUCAAUCAUAUAAAAAUAUAUCAUUUCAGUAAUGAAUAUACUUUUGUAUUUUUUUCUUGAUAGGGUUACCAUCUUCAAUAGACUGAGAUAACUUUAUAGGACUCUGGACUGAGACCUGAUUACAAAAUAUUUGAAUUUCAAUGCCAUCUCUGUCACUAACUUCCUGGGUCAAUGCACAAGGCAUGUACUAAUGAACUGAAUUUUCUCAAUGCCUGAGUUACUUCCUGAGAGUAAAUUAGUCAUUAGAGAUUCUAGUUCAAAUUUGCCUGUAUUUCUUCCCCUGACUUUAUUUUUCCUGUGAUAUCAGUGUUUAAUCUACUGUGUAAGAUUACUUGCUGCUUGCGAGGCUUGCACAUGUUCUAAGAAAAAUUGUUUUCUUGUUAGCAUCAUUCAGUUAAUUUGAAGGUUCUCAAAGCAAGGCAUUUCGGGGGGAAUAAUAUUUACAUAAUUUAAAUUGUUUUCAAGUUUAUAUACAAAAACUGUUAAUACCACCAUCUAUAAAAAUGGCCAAAGACUUUGUAGCAAAGAAUAUUACUCCAUUUUUAUAAGAUUAAAGAGUACAUUUUUUCUCCCUAAAGAAACAAUUUGAAUAAGACCUGACCCCUUCCCCUUCAUUUUUCAAUGGUGUGUGGUCAAAUUGAAUUCUCCAUUAAAAAUUCUCUAAUAUCUUUUUUUGCAUUAACAUUUCAAAACUCAAUUUAAAUAUUCACAGAUCUCGUUUUUAAUAAACUUAACGAAAUUCAGGUAAUUUCCUUCAACUUUCUUGAUUGAAGGACAGCAGUUGGUACAGAUAUAAAAAAGAGGUACAGCUAUGAGCAAAAGCCCAAAAUCAAUUAUAUAUAAGAAAUAACAUAACACAUGGAAAGAAAUUAAUCAAAAAGAAGAAUUUCUACCAUAUGAUUCUCUGGUCUGCUACCUGCAGGCAACAAAUGUAAAUGAAAAAAAAUCAACAUUCUUCUGGCAGACAAGAGAAAAAUUAAUAAAAAUGUUUCCUUCCUACUAGAUCCCCUGAUGCCACUAUUGUUAAAAGUGAGUGACUGCAGGAAGAACUUGCUCAUUUAAAAUAGUAUUUUUUUUUUAGACUACAGAAAUAAGAUUUUAUUCUUGCUGUUAAGCUCAAUUACAUGAGUUAGUAUGGGUUUGCACUGUCCAAAGAGUGUCCCUCUUCUCUGCCCCUUCUCAUUAAAUGGCUCUGUGGGAUAUGCAUGAGACAAAUGUAAUAGGAACCGAGUGAGAAGCAUUUUGAGGUGUGCCUACAGGGUAAUGAUUCAUAAGAAAGUCUGUGUGUAGCAGCUGAGAACUCUGAGAGAGGAACUACUAAGAGCCACAAGAUAUGCCCCAGAUAAAAUUAGUAAAAACGUAUUAGUAAUUUCAAGCUAGAAACGUUCCUACUGCAUAAUUAAGAGAGGAGGGGAACGUUUUCCUGGGAUUUAGCUUUUUAAUUUAGAGUCGGGUUAUUUUUUUCCCCAAUACUAAUUGAACAAACAGGAUAUAUACGUACAGAACAUAUCAUACUAAAAUUUUCCUAUUAGAAGAGCUUUAUAUUUUGUAUUUUGUGAAUGUUAUCCUGAAAUUAACAGAAAUACAAGCCAAGAAUACAGAUUGUUAGGCAAGGAGUCAUCCAAUUUUAGUGUCAGUCCACUCCUUCCUUUUCAUCACAUAGAAUAUGUAGCAAGUUUAAAAUGAAAAGUUAUAUUUUAACUCCUUUUACCUAUCAACUAAAAUAGAGUAUACCUAUGUAGAGUUUUGAUAUAUUUGUGUAUUUAUAUAUUAAUCAUGAACCAGAAUUUGUUUAUCCCUUUUUUAUAUGUAUAUUUUGAAAGGUAGCAUCAUUUGACAAAUGUGGCUCGAUUAUGAUGUCACAAUUCAAACAUUAUAUAUAUAUAUAUAUAUAUAUAUACACACACACACGCACAUAUAUAUAUAUCUCGUGUUUAAAUAUAUAUGUAUGUUUCUUCAAUUGUAUGAUUUGGAGGUUCCUUUUGUUUUAUAUACAUUGGAGAUCUUUCUUUGCCUGUCCAUUCCUUUGUGUGAGUUGGACCUUUUGAAAAAGAGUUCAAAAGAGCAUAAAACAGGAGCUGGCAACUUGGGAGAACACCACCAUUUUCAUUUUCAUUGAUUAAGAUCUUGAGAAAUGUAUCCCAUUGACAUAGAUUCUUUGUUCUGUGCACAAGUAAAAUGACAUAAAGUUUGUGAUGAAAAUUUUAAUUUUUAAUAUUAAUAAUGCUAUCUGAUAUUAAAAUGAUCCAAAAUGGGAUACAUUGGGAAGCUCUGGAAUAAAAAGGUUUGGAAAUAUUUGUGUGUUUUCGGGGCAAAUUCACCUAGUGGAAUUUCUGUGCACACUGUGAUGGAUUAUUGUAAUUAUUGGGAAUGAUAAUAUUUUAAUGUGACUUUCAUCCCACCUGUCAGUUGCAAUCAAGGCUGCCCAGUAUUCUGAAACAAUCUCAUUUUGCUAGGUGGCUAGUCUUGUGCAGCUUCUAGAAUGCUUAGAAUAUUAAUGCAUGAAGAGGAGAUUGAAUGCUUUCUGUAGUUCCAUAAUGACAGAGUGUCUUGUUUUAAUCAAAAGGCAUGCAAUAUCAAGCUAAAGUAAUGUAUAAUACAUUAAUGCCAAUAACUGUUUAAGAGAGAAGAUCCCUUUUGGGGGAUAUUAUAUCAGAACCAUAGAAGUUGGCAUUUCUUUCCCCUAUUAAUACAUGAUAAUGUAUAUUAAUUUUUGUAGAACUUAAUUUCAUCUUAGAUGCUUCUUAUUCUGAAGUGCUUUGAAUUUACCUGAACAAAGACAAUCUGACAUUUAGGUGAGGAUUGUUGUUCCAUUUAUAGUAGGCUACCAAAGUAGAAAGUUAUUAUUGAGACAAUGUCUGUCGAAAGACAUAUGUAUUUGACUUAAUAUUUACUAUGUUGUUCUUUAUCAUUUCUUGCAUUUUCUCAUUGUUUUGCUUAUUUUGCAUCAUUUUCAUCCUUAUUCCUCAGAAUGCCUAUAUGUUUUCGCAUCCCCCCCUUUUUUUUUUCUGAAAUUUUCUUUGUCACCUUCUAGCUCUUACUCCAGUGGCUAUGGAUGCAUUUCAGGGUUUUCUUUAGCCCCCUGAAAUUGUAGCAAUAAUUUUCUUAUAAAUUCAUUUAUCUGGGGGACUAAGUGCUCCAUUAACUGCUUCUUAACCAUGCAAAUCCACUUUUUAAAAUUUCAUUUUAUUCAGCUAUUACAUUACCAGUGUAUAGGGUUAGACUAUUUAAUCUUUAAUGCCCCAUUUGUCAUUUACAAACUGCAGAUCAUUGAAACAACCACCAAAUGAAAAAUCAUCCGAUAUACCCACCUUAGGCCCAGAUUGCACAGCGCAGCUGUUGGUACUGACUAGAUGAAAAGCUUCACUGUACAUUGGGCUGUCCAUCAGCAUCGUCAGUUUCCCUGAUUCUUUUUCAAGGGCCGCUUGAAGAUGCCAUUGAAGAUGAGGAAGAAGAAUGUCCAUCAGAGGAAACAGACAUCAUCUCCAAAGGAGACUUUCCAUUGGAGGAAAGCUUUUCCACAGAAUUUGGGCCUGAAAAUCUGAGCUGCGAAGAAGUGGAAUACUUUUGUAACAAAGGUGAUGAUGAAGGAAUCCAGGAGACAGCAGAAUCAGAUGGGGACACACAGUCAGAGAAACCGGGGCAACCUGGAGUUGAGACAGACGACUGGGAUGGACCAGGAGAGCUGGAGGUGUUUCAGAAAGAUGGGGAACGAAAAAUUCAGAGUCGACAGCAACUUCCAGUGGGAACAACCUGGGGGCCGUUUCCUGGGAAGAUGGACUUGAAUAAUAAUUCUUUGAAGACAAAGGCUCAGGUCCCAAUGGUGCUGACUGCUGGUCCCAAGUGGUUGCUGGAUGUGACUUGGCAAGGAGUGGAAGACAACAAAAACAACUGCAUUGUGUACAGCAAAGGGGGUCAGCUUUGGUGUACAACUACGAAGGCCAUCUCUGAGGGUGAAGAGCUAAUUGCCUUUGUGGUGGAUUUUGACUCAAGGCUACAAGCUGCCAGUCAGAUGACUCUCACAGAAGGGAUGUACCCUGCACGCCUGCUGGACUCAAUUCAGCUGCUUCCUCAGCAAGCUGCCAUGGCUUCUAUUUUGCCCACAGCUAUUGUCAAUAAGGAUAUAUUCCCUUGCAAGUCCUGUGGCAUCUGGUAUCGGAGUGAGCGGAAUCUGCAGGCCCAUUUGAUGUACUACUGCAGUGGGAGGCAAAGAGAAGCUGCUCCGGUGUCAGAGGAAAAUGAAGACAGUGCCCAUCAGAUUUCCAGCCUGUGCCCCUUCCCACAGUGCACCAAGAGCUUUUCAAAUGCUCGAGCUCUAGAAAUGCACCUGAAUUCACACAGUGGAGUGAAAAUGGAAGAAUUCCUGCCCCCUGGUGCUAGUCUAAAAUGCACCGUCUGUAGCUACACUGCUGAUUCCGUGAUCAACUUUCACCAACACCUGUUCUCCCAUCUCACUCAAGCUGCCUUCCGAUGUAAUCACUGCCAUUUCGGCUUCCAGACUCAGAGGGAGUUAUUGCAGCACCAGGAGCUCCAUGUCCCUAGCGGCAAACUUCCCAGAGAAAGUGACAUGGAACACUCUCCAAGUGCAACUGAAGACAGCUUACAGCCAGCCACAGACUUAUUGACCAGAAGCGAACUUCCCCAGAGCCAAAAGGCCAUGCAGACUAAAGAUGCGAGCUCUGACACAGAGCUGGACAAGUGUGAGAAAAAGACUCAGCUCUUUCUCACGAACCAGAGACCAGAGAUACAGCCUACAACAAAUAAACAAAGCUUUUCUUACACAAAAAUAAAGUCUGAGCCCUCUAGCCCAAGACUUGCCUCAUCUCCAGUUCAGCCUAAUAUUGGGCCUUCUUUCCCUGUGGGCCCUUUCCUAUCUCAGUUUUCUUUCCCCCAAGAUAUCACCAUGGUCCCUCAAGCUUCAGAGAUCUUAGCUAAGAUGUCUGAACUGGUGCAUCGGCGACUGAGGCAUGGCAGUAGUAGCUACCCUCCCGUCAUUUACAGCCCUUUGAUGCCCAAGGGGGCUACUUGUUUUGAGUGUAACAUAACAUUCAAUAAUUUGGAUAAUUAUCUAGUGCACAAAAAGCAUUAUUGCAGCAGCCGAUGGCAGCAGAUGGCUAAGUCCCCAGAGUUCCCUAGUGUGUCAGAAAAGAUGCCUGAAGCUUUGAGUCCCAACACUGGCCAAACCUCCAUAAACCUUCUCAACCCAGCUGCUCAUUCUGCUGAUCCUGAGAAUCCACUUCUUCAAACAUCUUGCAUCAAUUCUUCCACUGUCUUAGAUUUAAUUGGGCCAAAUGGGAAGGGCCAUGACAAGGACUUUUCCACUCAAACUAAGAAGCUCUCCACCUCCAGUAACAAUGAUGACAAAAUUAAUGGAAAACCUGUUGAUGUGAAAAAUCCCAGUGUCCCCUUAGUGGAUGGGGAAAGUGACCCAAAUAAGACUACCUGUGAAGCUUGCAACAUUACCUUCAGCCGGCACGAAACAUACAUGGUCCACAAACAGUAUUACUGUGCUACACGCCACGACCCUCCACUGAAGAGGUCUGCUUCCAACAAAGUGCCUGCCAUGCAGAGAACCAUGCGCACACGCAAGCGCAGAAAGAUGUAUGAGAUGUGCCUACCUGAGCAGGAACAAAGGCCUCCACUGGUUCAGCAGAGAUUUCUUGACGUAGCCAACCUCAAUAAUCCUUGUACCUCCACUCAAGAACCCACAGAAGGGCUAGGAGAGUGCUACCACCCAAGAUGUGAUAUCUUUCCAGGAAUUGUCUCUAAACACUUGGAAACUUCUCUGACGAUCAACAAGUGUGUUCCAGUUUCCAAAUGUGAUACUACUCAUUCCAGUGUUUCCUGCCUAGAGAUGGACGUGCCCAUAGAUCUCAGCAAAAAGUGUUUAUCUCAGUCUGAGCGGACGACCACGUCUCCCAAAAGGCUGCUGGACUAUCACGAGUGCACUGUGUGCAAGAUCAGUUUCAAUAAGGUAGAAAACUAUCUGGCCCACAAGCAGAAUUUCUGCCCGGUUACUGCACAUCAGCGUAAUGACCUGGGUCAACUGGACGGCAAAGUGUUUCCGAAUCCAGAAAGCGAACGAAACAGCCCUGAUGUCAGCUACGAAAGAAGCAUAAUAAAAUGUGAGAAAAAUGGGAAUUUGAAGCAGCCUUCCCCCAAUGGAAACUUAUUUUCAUCCCACCUAGCAACCCUGCAAGGCUUGAAGGUCUUUAGUGAAGCUGCUCAGCUCAUUGCUACAAAAGAAGAAAACAGACAUUUGUUUCUUCCACAAUGCCUUUACCCUGGAGCAAUAAAGAAAGCAAAAGGAGCCGACCAGCUUUCUCCAUAUUAUGGAAUCAAGCCAAGUGAUUAUAUUUCUGGUUCUCUUGUCAUCCAUAACACUGACAUCGAGCAAAGCAGAAAUGCAGAAAAUGAAUCUCCUAAAGGCCAGGCUUCCUCAAAUGGGUGUGCUGCGCUGAAGAAAGAUUCUCUGCCAUUGUUGCCCAAAAAUCGAGGAAUGGUAAUAGUGAAUGGUGGACUGAAACAAGAUGAGAGACCUGCUGCCAACCCACAGCAAGAGAACAUUUCCCAGAAUCCUCAGCACGAAGACGACCACAAAUCUCCCUCGUGGAUCUCUGAGAACCCAUUAGCUGCCAAUGAGAAUGUCUCACCAGGAAUUCCCUCAGCAGAGGAACAGUUGUCUAGUAUAGCAAAAGGUGUGAAUGGUUCCAGCCAGGCUCCAACCAGUGGGAAAUAUUGCCGGCUAUGUGAUAUCCAGUUCAACAACCUUUCAAACUUUAUAACUCACAAGAAGUUUUAUUGCUCAUCACAUGCAGCAGAACAUGUCAAAUGAACUAACUAAACAUCAGUCACCUUUGGUAUCAGUGUUUAGUAUGUUGUUCUAACCAGUCCAGAAAAAAAAAUAAGCUGUUUGAAUUACAUCUGGGCAAUCAGGAGAUAAUUCAUUAUGGCUGAGUUGAAGACUUAAGGUGUAAUUUCAUUACAGUCCAUUAGUAAAGUGUAUUAUUGGUGCCAUUUUCAAAAAAAUUAAUUUAUUUUACCAGCAGUAUUCAUAGCUGUGGUUAUGUUAUUUUUUAUUUAAAAACUUUAUAUUAAAGUCAUUUGUAAUGUUAUUGUAUAGUUAUUGUGUAGCACAUAUGGUUUGCACUGUAUAGUAGCUUUUAAAGAAAAUAGUCACAAUACAGAAAAGCAUUUUAGAAAUAGCUUCAAAAGCACUUGUGUAUCUUGAUUUUUUCUUAUAUGCUGUUGCAGAUAUAUGUAUAUGCUAAAAUAUAACUUGCAAAGAUGUUCUAAAUACACAUGCUAUAAGUUCGCCUUAAGAUUUCAAUUCUUGGAUAAUCAGGCUCUGUUUGCACUUUAUAUUUUAGCAGAUACAGUCUCUUAGUCACUAGGCUUUGCAUUUGUAUGUAGCUGUAUGUUUCCGUCCAUUUUCUUAAUCCUGAACCUGUAUGUUAAAUGAAGAUGGCAAUUUUUUUCUUGUAUAGUACUUGUAUUUUCUUUCGCUGAUGCAGCUCUGUCUCAAUUUUUAAACCUUUGCUGUUAAAUGCAAUACUUUAUAAAGAAUGAACAAAAUUACUGGAAGCAGUAUUGUAAGUAAUGAGGUAGUAUUAAUCAGUUUUAUCUUUUGAAAGGCACAGUCUAAAUCGAAACCCUAAACUCAAUGCUGCAAGUAUGAAUUUAAUUCAUAUAUAAGAUCUAUUUAAAUAUAAGAGUAGCAAUACUGCACCUGGUGAUCACAAAGAUAAUGUUCUACUUCUGAUAGAAAUAAUUUCUCAACAAAUGUUGUUACUAUGCAUGUAUAUGGAUGGAAUAAAAUUCCAGAUUGUUGGAGAA